UUGAACUCCUGAGCUCAGGCGAUCCUCCUGCCUCUACCUCUCACAGUGCUGGGAUCCCCCACUGUGCCUGGCUAUGUUCUGCUUUUUCUCCACGAUGAUCACCCACCUGCAUUUCCAUGUGUCCACACUGUCCACAUGGUCGCCCUCUCCCAGGUCCAGUAGCACUGUCCACUCAAAGGGGUCCAUUCUCAGCCACGGAGAUCCUCCCGGGUCCACUCGGCCAGACAGGUCCUCCCAGGUCCGCUCAGCCACACAGGUCCUCCCAGGUCUGCUCUCGGCCACAGAGGUCCUCCCGGGUCCGCUCUCGGCCUCAGAGGUCCUCCCAGGUCCGUUCUUGGCCACAGAGGUCCUCCCGGGUCUGCUCUCGGCUUCAGAGGUCCUCCCGGAUCUGUUCUUGGCCACAGAGGUCCUCCCGGGUCUGCUCUCUGCCACAGAGGUCCUCCCGGGUCUGCUCUCUGCCACAGAGGUCCUCCCAGAUCCGCUCAGCCACAGAGGUCCUCCCAGGUCCGCUCUCAGCCACAGAGGUCCUCCCGGGUCCACUGUCAGGCACAGAGGUCCUCCCGGGUCUGCUCUUGUCCACAGAGGUCCUCCCGGGUCUGCUCUUGUCCACAGAGGUCCUCCCGGGUCUGCUCUUUGCCACAGAGGUCCUCCCAGGUCCGCUCUCAGCCACAGAGGUCCUCCCGGGUCCGCUCUCAGCCACAGAGGUCCUCCCGGGUCUGCUCUCUGCCACAGAGGUCCUCCCAGAUCCGCUCAGCCACAGAGGUCCUCCCAGGUCCGCUCUCAGCCACAGAGGUCCUCCCGGGUCCACUGUCAGGCACAGAGGUCCUCCCGGGUCUGUUCUCGGCCACAGAGGUCCUCCUGGGUCUGCUCUUUGCCACAGAGGUCCUCCCGGGUCUGCUCUUUGCCACAGAGGUCCUCCCGGGUCCACUGUCAGGCACAGAGGUCCUCCCGGGUCUGCUCUUGUCCACAGAGGUCCUCCUGGGUCUGUUCUCGGCCACAGAUGUCUUCCCAGGUCUGCUCAGCCACAGAGGUCCUCCCAGGUCCGCUCUCAGCCACAGAGGUCCUCCUGGGUCCGCUCUCGGCCACAGAGGUCCUCCCGGGUCUGCUCUCUGCCACAGAGGUCCUCCCAGAUCCGCUCAGCCACAGAGGUCCUCCCGGAUCUGCUCUCGGCCACAGAGGUCCUCCCGGGUCUGUUCUCAGCCACAGAGGUCCUCCCGGGUCUGCUCUCAGCCACAGAGGUCCUCCCGGGUCCACUGUCAGGCACAGAGGUCCUCCCGGGUCUGCUCUUGUCCACAGAGGUCCUCCCGGGUCUGUUCUCGGCCACAGAUGUCUUCCCAGGUCUGCUCAGCCGCAGAGGUCCUCCCGGGUCUGCUCUCGGCCACAGAUGUCUUCCCAGGUCUGCUCAGCCGCAGAGGUCCUCUCGGGUCCACUCUCGGCCACAAAAGUCCUCCUGGGUCUGCUUUUGGCCACAGAGGUCUUCCCAGCAUUUCCGUCAUCAGCUCGAAGCAGUCGGUUCUUCCCAGAGCUUCCAUCGUCAUCUUCUGGAACAUGAUCUUCUCUGCACUGGUUACUUUUGCUUUUUGAGUGAAACUCUUAGGGUCUGUUUUUAAGGGGAGGUCCAGGCCAAGGGACGUGUAAGGCUGCGUGCCCGUCCUCCAGUGCUUUGGCUCCGGGUGAACAGCGCCACAUCCCUGUGUGACUGAAGCCGCCGCGCUGCUGCCAGCAUCGCUCUCUGCAGCUGCCCCUCCGCACUUCCGAUCACGUGAAUUGAUCUUGUGGGCUGGCAGAAGCUGGAUUCUUUUCCCUUAUUACUAGAGAAAUACUUACUUUAGAAAUUACAAAUGAGUGACAAAGAAGAGAAUUUCAGUCGUGUAAAACGCAGUCACCUGGAAAUGGCGCUGACUCACGGCUGCGAAGCCCCCAGGGUCUGGGGCUGCCCUCGAUGGAGAGGGUCACAUACGUGAUGUUGGAGGCAGCACCCGCCCUUUGGCAGGUGUGCACGUGGAUUUCCCAAAAGGGUCUCCACCACGAAAUUCUCCUAACACCCGCGUGUCAGCACAUGUUCCUUACGGUUUUAUAAAAUGUGGUCAUUGGUAUAAUUUUCUCUCUGGCAGAGAGUUUCAUGCUGUUGAUAUAUAGUAAUUUCUUUAGAAAGCAAUGGUAAGUUAUGUUCUUUUAUCACAAGGUUACCAUUAGUGGAAGAGUCUUUGAUUUUAGUAUUCAGGAUUUCUUUAAACUGUUUCCUUUUGCUUUUACUUUUCACGUAAGCUUGACUAAACACAUUACUAGACGGUAGGUAUUUAGUGACUCUAGAGUUCUACUAAAGGAUCAUUCUGCAAUUAUGCAGGUUUUAAGGAGAAGCAAGAGAAAUGGAAACUGGGUAGUUUGUAGCCGAAUGAUUGCAGAAUCAAAUGGGGGCUUAAAACUCAAUGUGAAUUUGUUUCUCAUUUUUCUAA